GAUAUUUUCCUGAACAAUCUGAAGUCACAAACACCACCUUGAAAUCUCCGGGAAGUCAAUGUUGCAAACUCACUUAAUUUUAUUAUUAAGUCUUGCCCCAUGAAAUAUUUCUGAGAUGGAGCCAACAGCCAAGGGACGGACUGAGGAGAGUUUCAGCUACGUCAUCAGAGCCCCCAGCAGUGAGGGGUUCGACAUAAUGAACGUUGAUGUGAAGAUUGACACAUCCUGGAUAUUCCAGGACAUGGAAGAUAGUGCUGAGGAGCGGGAAUGUCUUCAGGAAGAAGCAGCUGGCCGCCCAGACAUGGAUAUGGGUGCGCUCAGGAGGCAGCUGGAGUCCUCCGAGCAGAAGCUGUCAGCAGCAGAGGACAAGUACGUGACAUCGGAGUCCGGGCUGAGAAGCAGAAUUCAGGAGCUGGAGCUGUCAGAAAGGAAACUCCUCCGGAAGGUGGACCAGCUGAGCACCCACGUGGCCCAGGAGAGAAGCGCCUGGCUCCAGGCCCAGGAGAAGCUGGCGGCGCUGCAGGGGGAGCUGGCCAGCCAGAUCCGGGAGGAGAGCGUGGCCAGGCGGCAGCAGUGGCGGCUGCGGCGGUUGCAGGAGCGGUUGCGGCGCAAGGACGAGGCACUGGGGCAGCAGGCGGCGGCCCUGGAGCGCUGCCGGCGGACCCAGCGGCGCCAGCUGGGCCUGGUGCGGGAGCAGGAGCGCGUCCUGCGGGAGCAGGUGCAGCGGCUGGAGCGCAACGUGCGGCGCCUCUGCCGCGCCGCGGGCCUCCUGCUGGCCCAGUGGGACACCGCGGCCCCAGGCUCCCAGGGCGCCACCGAGGCGGCUGCGGAACUGCGCGCCCUGCAGGCGAGGGCAGAGCGCAGCGAGCGCGAGCGGGAAGAGGCGGCGCGCAGCCUGCAGGAGCACCGGGCCACCGAGCGCCAGCUCCGCGGGCAGCUGGAGGAGCUGCGCUGCUGCAUCUAUGGGCUGAAGCUGUCAGAGAUUGGCCUGCAGGGCCAGGUGGAGGACCUCGCCCAGCAAAACCAGUGCCUGCGAGAGGAGCUGGGAGCCCAGGCCCCUAUUGGUCACUGCAGCCUGGAUGCUCUGGGCUGUGUUCAGGGUGACUCACUGCCCCUGCCCAGGGAGGAGGCCCUGGACCCCUGCAGAAGCCAAGACUGGCGGAACUCCCUGCGGUCCAAUGAUGCACCCAGACAAAGGGCCCCAGCAGGCCAGUCCCCAGAGGGGCCCUGCACCUGGAGCCGCAUCAGGCCUGGACGGGCCUCUUCUGUUUUGGCUCCAGGCCCGGAGACCACAAGCGAGCUCCCCAGAGACCUGGCCGGAUCCAACCGUGAACAGCUUACUCUGGCAGAGCCCAGCUUGGAUGAACAGAUUCUUCUCCUGGUCUGUGGCUGCCCACCAGAGGAGUGCUUGGACGAGUCACUCCUCCGCAUGGACCUGGCCUGGAUUUCAGAGAAUCUAGCAGCUGACCCAGCUGCAGAAGCCUUUCUCCUGGUGCAGACAUCCGCACUCCCUCUCUGGGGGCCGGCUGGGGACUCCGCUUCUUGGCGACCACUGCUGCUCCAGGAGGUUCCCUCAGAUGGACAAAAAAUCCAAGAAGAGUUGGCCACCAGGUCCCCGCCUCCUCCCAAAGCCACAGGACACCCAGGCUGGGAUUGUCACCAGACAAGAGGCCGCGGUGCCUCCCUCUUCCACGAGGCCCCCUACAUUUCAAAUCACCCAUUUCUGAAAAAACACCCCAAGGAUCUGAAAGACACUUGGAACAAUGGAGGAGGAAGCCUUGCGGGGAGAACUGAAGAGGGGAAGGCAAGGGGGACUUUGGGCAGGAAGGGGAAAAACCUUGGUGACAAGUACCAGCUAAGUCAGGAAAGCCAUCAGAACCUGAGCUUGGAGAAUGGGGCUGGAGCUGCAGAGGACGUGCAGGAUCAGAAUGGGGCUUCAGAGACUAAGGCCGCCACCUGCCGCCCUGGGUCCUGGCAGGAGUUUUUGAUGCCUCUUCUACAGGGGGAGGCCUCAGUAUCAAAGGAGGGUCCCGAAUCCCUGAGCAGGAGGGAAAGGGUGGAAGGAUACGUCUGGGGUCUCCGAGGAGGACUGUCAUCAGAGAAUGAGGAAGUGGCACCCCCAGCCACCUUCUCCAGGGCUCAUGAGACCAAAGAGCCAUGGCCAACAGACAGUCAGCUCCUCGCAGGGAAAGUCAGAGCCACUGGGAGGACAGCUAGGGGCAAGGAGGAAAACCAAGUGUGGCUUGGAAAUGCUCUGCUUCUGCAAGGAGGAAGCCUGGAGGACAAAGGGCUAGAGGAAGAGGAUGAGAUGCCGCAUCAAGAAGCAUCCGGUCUGGGGUGCAGGGGUGCCCCCGAGGAGCCUGACUCCCAGGAACAUGAGAGCAAGGAAAUGCUUUUCUUUGCAGGAGAGACAGGUUUGCCACUGUUUCCCAGAUUUGCCUUAUCAGUUGAAGGGGCCGAACCCACUGAUCAUGGUCAUCCACAGGCUGUGAGCAAAGGACACAACAGGUGUGCACUCACAAUCGAUGAGCUUGCACAGGACGUGGAGGCUUGUUUCCAGCAGCUGUCCACCCUGCAGCCGGGCAGCAGGGGCUGGCAGUGCUCAGCCUCUGCAUGUAGGGGAGAGAACUGGAGCUUUGCUCAGAAGUGGCACAGUGGCUGGGAGAGAGCUCACUCUCAGCAGGUUUGGGGAAAUUGGGGUAUUUGUUCUAAUGAAGAAGCGAAGUCUAAAGAGAGUGGUGAAGGUGAUAAGCCGGGAAAGACCACGGCCCUGGGCACCAGCGAAGUUCCUGGUAACCCAGGGACACUGCCUCAUUGGGAUGAAGCCAGCCCAAACCCUCCACAGGGGCCUGCUGAGCCCUGGGGUGCCCUCGAGAGAGUGAGGAGCAGGUUUCAUCAGCUCAUUUCUGGAUUGAAGAAACAGAGAAGCCAGAUUUUACAUGACAACACCAAACUUCACGGAGACCAAGAGAGGUUCCAUGAAAGAGUGUGCGCCCUUGAAAGAGAGAGAGAGAGAGAGGUGACAAAAAUAUCCAGGCUCGAGCGGGAUAACCACAGGCUGGUAGGGGACAUCUCUCAGUUAAAGAAAGAACUGGAUCAAUAUUUACAGGCAAUCUCUGACCUUGAAGACUGCAAUGGGAAGAGUUACUGCAAAAUUUUGGAGCUUGAAGAGGAAAAUGAAACACUGAAAGGGAAUCUGGGCCAACUCCAGAAAGCCACGUCUGAGAGUGUCAGGAAAUCCAAAGACACGAUGGAGCAAGUCACCCUGGAAAACUGGAAGCUCCAGACACUGAUCUCGGAGCUUGGCGUCAGUUAUAAAGAGCUGAUAAAGGAUAUCGUGCUAGGAAUAGAAGACAUGAUCCGGGCCUUAAGUGGGGAGAACGAGCACCUUCUACGCAGGGUCCAUGUCCUGGAGAGGGAAGUCACCUUGCAGAGGAGCACGGAUCAGGGGCGUUUGGUGAGGGGAAGGGAGCACCUCCAGGGAAAAGCCAAGAUGCACGCUCUAGACAAAGAGGUGCAGGUGACUCCACUCACAGGACAGCUGCUUUCAAGAGCCUGUGGGCCACCCUUGGAGGAGGAAAUGAGUCUGGCUGCAGGGCAGACAGGACCUUCCACAGGCACCGGGAAUUCCAGACGCGGUGCUGAUUCUCCCCCUCCAUCGCUGGUCUGGAGAAACACUGGUGUAGCCAAUGCCCUGCAAGGAAAUGUCAGUGGAGCAGAAGUGAAAGAAGCACAUUUGGAGAAAGAGGAGAAGAGGCCCAGGUGUUCUGUGGCUCAGGGGCAAGCUCUGAGCUCCCUGAGCAAUGGCCCCAUGCUCCGGGACUCAGAGGCCGAGGUUACUGAGGAGGAUCCCAGGCUGCGGGCCCAGCAGCUCCAUCACCGGGUGCUGACCCUGCAGUGCCAGCUCAGGGACCAGGGCGCUGCCCACCAGGCGUCUCUGGACGAGGCCACCCGCCUCCAGGAGGAGCUCCAGGCCAAGCUUGAAGAACUUCAGAAAAAGCAACAUGAAGCAAAGUUGGCAGUGACUCCCCUGAAGGCCAAGAUAGCUUCCCUCGUCCGGAAGUGCCGGGAGAGGAACCGCCUGAUCACCCACCUGCUGCAGGAGCUGCACAGACAUGGGCUGGGGAACCUCCUGCUCUCCGAGCUGGCGCAGAACAUGCUCAACGACGUGGCACUGGCUGAGUACACGGCCACCUUCCUGGCUCCGGGAGUCCCAGAGACAAGCCACCACCUGGACGUCAAGUCUGAGAUGACGGCAGCUUUAAGAGCUCAGACAUACCUCUUGAAUCCUGAAAUGGACAGUGUCCUCCAAAGCUCAUUGUCUUCAGAGUCCUGGCCUAUUCCCGAGCCGGAGUGGCCAGCACAGACAGCCCAACUGGAUUCUCUGAAGCUCCCUCUGUCCUUGGUGUCCACGCUUGAUCCUGGAACGUGCCUGGCAGCGGUCACUGUGGAACCAGGUCUCCCCGCACAACGUCUGCAAGAAAAAGGCGGAAUGCCCUGUCCUGCCCUCCAAGUCGAUAACGUCCCAGCACCCUCUGAGCUCCUGAGCCCAGCAAGGAUCCUGGCUUUUCACCAAGAGCUUAGACAAAGCAUUUGCAGCAAUUCCCAGGUCCAUAAAUCACCGCUGGAGUUAGAAAUGUAAUAGGGCCACUCAUUCUCCGGAGCCAUUUCAUAGACUCCAUAAAUAUUUGAAGCAGAACCUUCAGAGAGUGCUUUAAGAAAUUGGUAGCAAUCAGAGCCCUCAUUUAGUGGCAAGUGGUUUUGCCUUCGGCUUUGGGAUUUUGUGUUCAUUGUCAGAGCUUGAGAGAAACGCUGGCCUGUGCCUGGCAAAUUCUGAGGAGUUUGGCUUUGGCAAUGUCAAGGCAGCAUAGGAAAUAUUUACUGUACCAAAACCUAUUGAAUGAUUGGUCCAGAGGUUCUCAACUGGGCACAGUUUUAGCCCCCCAGGGAAAAUCUGGCCAUGUCUGGAGACAUUUUUGGUUGUCACAGCUGGGACACUGCUACUGGCAUCUGGUGGGUAGAGGCCAGGGAUGCUAUGAAAUGUCCUACAAUACCCAGGCCAGCCUCCUACAGCAAAGAAUUACAGCCCGAGGGUCGCCAGUGCUGAGGUCGAGAGUCCAGGACGGAUCUCAUAGCUCCCAACAAGAUCAGCCAUGGAGAAUUGUUUUGUUUUGUUUUUUCUCUGCCCCCGGGGUCCUUCCCAUGUUUUAAAAGAUUUUUUGUCUACUAAGUGAAACGCCUAAGUCACCAUAUAUUUUACAUUUAAAAACAUUAAAACUAACCAGAACUUUCUAAUCAGUCCAUCCACUCCAAAAACGUCUGUUGAUAUCCACUGGAUGCCAGGCAAUGUGGCAUGAAGGAGAAGAGACAAGUCAAUGUUGAUCCUGGCGCCGGGGACCUCACAGGACAAUGGGAGAGAUACUCCUGUGAGUAAAUCAGCACGCACGCAAGUGUCACAUGUGCCCUGAGCAACGGGAUGAAGGUAAGGGUCCGUUCUACUUGGCUUGGGACAACUGGAAGUCAGCCACAAAGGAAUGGCUGGGCAGUGUCCGGUGGGUGAGGUGGGAAGGGUGCUGCUGUACGAGGGAACGCAUGUGCAAAGGCCCUGAGGCAUAAAACUGAACUGUGGAUGUGCCCCUGGAGGGGAAGUGGGCAAAGCAUGCUCUUGUCAAGCCAGCUGCAAGCAGUCACUGCAUCGUUCCCAUCCAGCACCCCUUCCUUCCACCGAGAACAGAGACUCGUGCCCCGAAUCAGGUGGGCGACCCAGGAGAAGAGCACUUCUAUCCUGAGGGCAGCCCCCCAAAAAGAGAGUCUAGGGGGCUUGGACGACACACACCAGACCCUGACCCAGGCUCACCCACCAGAGAUGUCACCUCUCUCUUUGGGAAGGGGCUGAGGAGGGGCUUAAGGGAAAGGCCAAAGCCGCUACCUGUCCAAUUCUGUCCUCUCCUGGAAGUGACUGUCCCUUCAUGGAAGGACAAACAAGGACAAGGACAAGGAACUGACGGCUCCCCAGGAAGUGUCAAAGUGUAUAGAUUUAUUUUAACGUAGUUUAGCUUUUUGUUUGAAAUGAAAAUUACACAGAGUUCCCGUAGACUCUUCCCCGGGCUUCCCUUGAUGUUAACAUCUCAUGUGACUUAUGUUGUACAAUUAUAGAAACUAGUGGGUUUUAUUUCGAGGAAAAUUGGGGAGCCAUUGAGACGUAAGAAAGGCAGCCUCAGCACAUUGAGUUCCACCCUUUAAAUUCGUUUAUGGGGUUUUCUGAUGGGUUAGCACAUUCAUCCAUGUAUUCCUGGAUUGAUUUACCCACAGAUCUGUCUAUUUAUUUAUUUAUUCAAUAUGCAUUUAGUGACUGCUGUGCGAGUGUCUGGCUGGAUGCUGCUGGGGAAGAAGUGAAGAUGAUGCUGUCCACCUAGGUUUUCAGGGACCCCCCUGGAGACCCUGUGGCCCCGUUACCACCCCUCAAGAAUCCCCAGAUUGGAAACCACUGCGGUGAUCCCUUUGUUGGUUCAACCACCCCAGGGCUUCCCUAUAAUUUCCAAGCAGGAAGUGACCUGCAGCACUGGUUUGGUGAUCCGCCUUCUGCCUCCCUCUGUAUUUUGGGACAAUGUCAUUAGCUUUGAGCAUCAGGAACAUGACAGAGAGAGGACAGAAACCCGGUGCAGCCGAGGACAGCCAGCUGAGCCCUUGCUGAGCCAGCGAGAUGCAGCGUGGUGCCACCACAUCUGGUCUCCAGGAGUCCCAGGAGCUCAGACGUCCGUCGUCUUGUGACUUCAUGCUCCCCUCUGCCGCGCUCACGUGCUGGGCCUGGGCAGAAAGGCAACCCAGGAAAUCCAUUAAAGCAAGCCAAGACGACCUUUGCAGCGUAACCCAACGAUUCCCUAAUAAAUCAUGUUUCCAAGGCAGAGCCACUUAUUCUCCCGGGCCAUGAAUUGCCGUCUGGGUCUAGCACUUUGGGUCGGCUCAAGCUUUGUGCCGUGGCUCCCUGGGGCACAGUACAGGAUGGCGGACUCCCCUCGCCUGGUCUGUAGACCCCAGCAUUUGGAAGGGCACAUGGUGGCUCCUUGCCACCCAUCAGAUGCUCCAGGGGCAGGACCUGCUCUGGCAACCCAGUAGGUUCAGGCAGGAACUUGGCACACAGGAGCUGGUCUCAGGCUGCCCCACAGGCAGGGAAUGACUACGAGUGACCCUGAGGCCUCUGGAGACCAGCCAGACGGUCCAGCCUGGCUCUGCAGCAGAAAACAAUUUGUCACACGGACUGUCAGCAAACAACAAUGGCGGACUUCCCUGGAGGCGGAGCCCUAAACCCUGCGAGGAAGGAAGACAGCACAGGGGCAAACAUAGCAAGCUGGAAAAUAUUUACAUCCUUCUCAACUGACCGACAGAGCAGAGGUGGCCUAUGAUUUACAAUCCUUUCCAGUGAGCCAAAUUAUAAGCCAAGCAACCAUCUUCCUGUCUCAAGUCACUAAUAGGGAAUACUUCUACUCUGUAUGAUACCAACCUGGGGACCCAAGAGAUGGCUGUUGACUGUAAGAAGCCCAUAUUUAAUGCCAUGUGAGUGACAGGAAGCCGGGUCUGGAGUCCCAAGGACCUGUCGGCUCUGCUGCUCCUACGCUGGGUCGCCGUGCACAAAUAACUUACCUUCUUCCAACAUCCUCUUCUUCGUCUGUUUGAGGGUCAUAUGCCUACUUGACAGUUUUGCUCUGACAACCAAAUGAGCUAAUGGCUGGAAAAGCACCUGAACACUGUAAGAUUCUUUCCAAGUGUCAGGAUCCUUGUUGUGUUUGUAAAAUGCAGUUCCUUCGACUUAGGUAUUUCACUGACGGUUGUCUCGGAGUGCACUCUGCCAUAAGGACUCAUUGAUUUACCAUUCUGCGUAGCUUCCAUCCAAGAUGGGUGAUGAGGGGAUGAUAGGAUGAUGGUUUUAAAAAAUCACUGUAGUAGUUAUCUUGAUAUUAUAGAGCUGCUGAAGAAGCUUGGGCUAGGAUGGAGUUCCCAACCUGCACAAAAAGUUGUAUGCAUGUGAACUCUUUCCUAGGGAGAAGGAGCAUGGAUUUCAUCAGAUUUGCAAAUAAGAUUGGUAGACAAGCACCCUAGUAGCCAAGCACCCCUAGUCUCGGCAGAAAGGACUCUGUCCGGAAAUCCAGAGACGGACUCUGCCUCCAACUUGCUGGCGACUUUAAGGCUGUCCCUUGGCCUCUAUCCGCCCCAGCUCCUUAUCUGUAAAAUGGGUGUGGCACAGUCUUCCAGUGGCUGAGUUCCUACUGAGGGGCAGGCUCUGGCCAGACAGGAAGCUUCCACACCCAGCCUUCUUGCUUCCAGAGUAAGCGAAGAGCUCUUCUUCUCUCAACUUGUGUCCAUGAGUUGCGCCCAACUGACCACAGCACCCCAAAGUGCCCAGGCAUGCAGCCUCAUUUCAGCUCCUUUUGCUCUGCAGUUAAAGAGCAUCACGGCCCAGUUGCUGUGCUUGGACCCAGGGAGUCUGCUUCCUCUGACACCAUUUCCCUGUAAACUGCAGGGCUGUGAGGCCCGCUUACACUGGCGGCCAGGGGCCUGACAGGGACCUGUGAAAUCUCAGCAUCGCCCAGGAAGAUGCAGUGAAAAUCCAGCUGUUGAGCGGGGAAACGUCAGUGAGCCACAUGUUUUCUUGCCCUGGCUGCUGUGAGACAGUGGGUGGUGACUGGAAGUCAGAUCUGGUGGUUGGAGUUGGCCAUGGGUGUCUCAGAUCUCCGCAGAACCUGGGGCAGUGGUCGGUGCUGGGUGAGCAACAGGCAGGCCCCAUAUCACAUUACAGACCUUAGAGAGUUUCCAGUCCACAGCGGGUACUGGCAGCCCUUGGGCCAGAUUUGGCCCACAAAUGUAUCAUGUUUGGCUUACAUUUACUUUUUUUAUAAUUGUGAAUGAGCUCUGUGCCACUGAGCUGGAUACUUAAAAAUGGUUAAGAAGGUAUGUUUCUCUAAAACUCUAAAACGUAUCUUCUUAAUCAUUUUUAAGUAUCCAUUUCAGUGGCACAGAGUGCAUUCACAUUGUGGUGCAACCAUCACCAUCAUCCAUCUCCAGAACCUUUUCAUCUUGCAAAAUUAGAAACACCAUAUUCAUGAAAGAUUCACUCCUCAUUUCCCUGUCCCACAGCUGCUGGCACCCACCCUUCUACUUCCUAUCUCUAUGAAUUUGACCACUCUAGGACCUCAUGUGAGUGGAAUCAUACAGUCUUUGUCCUUUCAUGACUAGUUUAUAUCACUUAGCACAAUGUUUUCGAGGUUCAUGUGGCAGCAUGUGUCAGAGUUUCCUUCCUUUUUAAGGCUGAAUAAUAUUCCAAUGUGUGGAUGUACCACAUUUUGUUUAUCAUUCACGCAUUGAGGGACCUUAGGGUGGCUUCCACCUUUUUGGCUACUGUGAGUAUUGCUCCUAUGAACACAGGUGUACAAAUGCCUAUGUUGCAUUUUUUAAUAUUGGAGUUAGCAAGUGACAUUUAAAAACCAAGAGAUUUCAUAUACAAAUCUGGAUUUCUGGCUUCUCUUGGAAAAUCAGUGUAUCUGACAGCAUCGGGCUUCCAUCUUCCUGGCCACAGUCAGAGGUGAAUGAAGCCAGCUCGCUCCCUCCCCCACUGAGAGGCACCCCACUCAGUGGACUGCAGGGCCCCCACUCCUUUCUCCUCCACUCACUGAAAAAGCUGCCUGGUUUCCACAGGCUAUGGCUUGGUGACACCUCGUCUGCUCAGCACCCAUCAUGUUAUGGGUGAAAAUGCAGAGGCCCAGGGAGGAAGGGUGGCUGGGGCCCGAGGUCUCACAGGCCAGGAAGUGAUACAACUGCUGAAAUGCAGGAAGGGCCUGCAACUGGGCAUUGCAAAGCCUUGAUUCUACUUCCAGCUCUGCUACCUGCUUGUCCCAGGUCCCUGGGACAAAGCCCUUAAACUUUCUGAACCUAAAUUUCCUCUUUGGAGGAAAAUGGGAGAAAUGGAACCUUCUAUUGCAGCCUCGUGAAGUAUUGUGAAGACAGAGGAGAUGUUGUGCAUUGACCAUUGAAUGCAAUUGGGAUGGGAAGGGGUGUUACUAAAAGCACAGGCCAUGUCAGGCAACCUAGCGUCUGGGGAUCUGUUUUCUCAUUUGCAAGACAGGAAAAGGGGCCACACCUUUCCCCACUGGGCUAUUACAAGGAUUAACUGAGGCAGGGAAAGAAAAGAAAAGCAUCCGGCAGAGGGCUUGGCACCCAGCAGAUGCUUCACAAAUGCUACUUCUUAACAAGUAAGGUCACGUCCAAGGGUUCCAAAUCCUCUUCCUGCAGUACACAACCCAGGAAGAGAUGUAACAUCAUGGGAACAACCAGCUUCAGAGUCUAUUGGCCUGAUUUCAAAACCUAAGCUUGACGCAUUAGCCACUGAGGGCACUGGGCAGGUGAGCCCAUCUCUCUGAUCUGCAAACUCUUCCAUUGUUUAGUGGGGAAAAUAUCACUGUCCUUGACAGCACAGGGGGAAAUGAGAAAUGGAAGGUGCUCUGCACAUAGUAGACAUUCAAUAGAGUCUAAUUCCUUUCCUUGCCUUCCCCAGCAGAGAUCUGUUUUCUAGGUUAAAAAGACGGCAUGUUUUCCAAAUAUCUUCAAAAAAGGGAACAAGGAAAAGUGUGGUUUCCAGCUUCCCACUGAGGUUUGUCAGUCACCAGGUUUCAUUCACUCAUUCAAGGAACAAGCACUGAUUGAGCACCACUAAGCGCCAGGCACCACAGUAGGCCCUGGGGUUCUGGGAGAGAACAGAGUAGGCCAAAUUGCUGCCCUGGUGGGUGGGCUUCCGCGUAAGUCUGCUCAGUCGCUCCAUGAGUACUCAUUAAGGGCCUCUUCUGAGCUGCCUUUCCAAGGGCCUUGGCUUUACCUGGAAGGCUCAUCUGUUGCUGUCUGUGUGAUUCCUGCAUAUCUGGACCUCACCCACUUCUCUGGCAGUACCAGAGAAUAUACCUGUCUUGGGCCCCAGACCUUUAGACAGCAUGGUGAUCCUGCCAGCCUGUGCUGCUUCGGUUAUCCCCUCAGUCAUUUCCAGGGUCCCUGGGCAAGGCCAAUGGAGCACUCCUGGGGUGAACAGUCCAUCCCACUGCACACAGGACACCCUGUGGGCCAGGUGUGGGCCCCGGAGAGCCUUGCCUCUUAGUUUACCUUUAGGCUUUGAAUGAAAUGGGAAUACGGAUGGAAAGCCCUUUGUAAACUCUUAAGAUCUACAUGUAUAUACAGGAUUGGUGUUAUUUGACUUUCUUCUAGAGAGAUGACAGAGACCACCCGAUGUAGGAGAAACAGGUUAGGGUUUAAGACCAGAAUAGCUAGGCUGCAAUCUGGGUUCUGCAAGUUAUUGGCUCCGAGACUAGGGAAAGUGGCCUCCCCUCCCCAGUUUACUUGCUGGGCAAAUGGAGAUAAUAAGAUACACACCUCGGCACCUACUGUGCGCAAUAAUGGAAAAACUGGAUGGGAAGGCAUUUUGCAGAAUUACAUGUUGUGCAUAUACUUUACUCAUGUCAUUAAUAUAAUGCACAUUUAUUAUACACCUACUGUGUGCCAUUAUGAACAAGGUGAUCUGUCAUAUGACAAUUUGGAAGAAAGUCCACAGGCUAAGGCAGAGAAGAAAUACUUGUCAGAUGGUUGUACUGCACAUUCAUAGAUUAUGAUUAGCAACAGCCAGCUAGUUGGCAUAGCAACGUUUCCCCAUGAACUGCUAGGCACUGUUCUUAAAAUAGGUAUGUCGGAGGUGUGGCGGCAGUGGGGACACGCUGAGGUAGUGUGGUUUGAUCGCUCUGCAGACCAAUGGGCUGCAACAAAUGCAAGACAUACAAAUGGUGACACACAUGGUGACAUACAGAGGGUGACACACAUGGGCUGUGUGCUCAGAGUGGCCCUGCCAUUGCCCUUCCCAGGCAAGCCAGCAGGUCAGUGAUUAAGGUGACAGAUCCGGAAACAUCCAUUGUUGGAGCUGGAGACAGCCUCAGACUUCAUCUAGUGUAAGCAUCCUUCUCCUCCCCAUUUUACAGGCGAGGAAACUGAUUCCCAGAUGAGGUUAACUGACAUCUGCGGUCCAGUGACAAAGCCACUUGACUGCAAAUGGGACUGAACGUGGUUCGGAUGUCAUUAUGCAGUAUUCUCCAACCGUGCCAUGGGGCAGGCUCUGCUGAUUCAGAAUUUUAGGUCUUGGUCUGAUGCAAUUAGUUUUCUACUGGGUUGCAAUCUAUAUGGCAUCAUCUAGUGAUAGAUGUUAGUUUAAGGAAUUCUUUCAUUUUGUGUGGAAUUCAUGCCUGCAUUUCGCCCUGGGGAAGCCCUGAAUCCCAGGAUAUCUUGGAAACUCACCUACUUUUUGGCUAGACUUACAUGAUUGAUCUUUAAAUCCACCCUUCCGUAGCCUUCCUUACCUAGUUUCUCGGUGUGAAAUCAAGCACCAAAGCUGGUCAAAGGUUUUUGAAUUGCUUUGGAAUGAGAUUAUUAUAUGAGUUUAGUUACCCAUCAUUGGAGAGAACAGGGAACGCAAGUCCUUUUACAGCUGGGGUCCUUUCUAUUUGUUUUACUCAGCAAUUUAUUGAGUAAACUUUUAUAAACUUGAGAGGGGCUUUUCAUCUUCAGGCUGGUGAGCUUCUUUUAAGAGAUUCACAGUUCCCCUUUGGUUCCAGGGUGAAAUUCUAGGUCUGAAACGUGAAACCUUCUGAGAACUCAGCCAACUUCUGAGAAUAGGGUGCGAGACAUUUCUGACAUAUUUUAGACACAACCUGUUUUUCUCUGUUGAGACAGUGUCAUGUGGUCGGAAGGGCUCUGGGCUGGGAGUCCAGGCAGGGUAAGAGGGGCUGCAGCCCUGCCACUUACCCCCUCCAGGUCAUUUGAAGGAUGUAAAGACCGCAUUCUGUACUGAUGAUUCUUCACCCUGGUUGCAUGUUGGACUCACCUGCAGAGCUUUUUAAAACACUGAUGCCCAAGCCUCUCUCCAGGCCACUGAAAUCAAGUUGUAUUGGGUGGGGCCCUGGGCAGAGAUCUAUUUGAAAAGCUCCCCAGUGAUUCUAAUGGGCAGCUGGGGGAGAACCAUGGGAAUACAGUCACAUAGUCUCUUUCCACUCCCCCAUUCCCUGUGCUAUUUAAGUUCUAAAAUGCUAUUGUGGGUUUCUUCUGUGCUAGACUCAUAUUUAUUUAUGCUCCUAGCUAGGAAAGAAAUGUGUCCUCAGAGUCUACAGGAGGAAACUUCUCAUCUCUGGAGAAUUUUUGACCAUGAGUUGGCUUUGUAACUCUACCCUCAGAGGGCCUUUUAAACAGCUGGUGGUUCUUAAAGAAAUGAAAUGCAUGAUGUGUUACUGCUUUGAGCUCCGCUGUGGCAGAGCCUGGAGCUGAGCUCUUGGUGACUGGUCACUGCACAAUUCCAUGAAAGUUCAGAUAAUAUAAUUGGGUGGUAAAUGACACACUAAAUGAAUCUCUUGGGUGCAGUUGUUUGCAUCCUAAACUCCAGAAUAUGCAGAAAGAGAUAUUCUGUGAUAGAUAUAUCUGCCAGUUGGGUAAGCAAACAAAAGUAGAUUUGUCUUCGGCAUGUGCACCAAUGGCAAACUGCAUUCCUACCUAGCUUUGAAAUAAAUUAUUGGAAGUUCUCUGGUGCCUUAAGGUGGUGUAGAAGGAAAAGAUCCCUGGGGUUUGUUAAUGUAUUUAGUCCUCUUCUCUGUGUUAUGGGAAUUUCUAAAAACAGAUAAUUUGUACGUUGGACCUAAAACUGCUUUCAAGAACUCAGUAGACUUGGGAUUGAAGGAUUGGGUUUUCUCUUUCCCAUGUGAACUUCCCUAAAUCCUACUCUGGCUUCAGAAAGCACAGCUCCUAUACAAGUCUGACUUCUGCAUUUUUAGUGUAAAUGUAAUGUAUUGAGUAAUGGAAAGACUAAUGGAAGAAUUGAUAGCUCAAAAAUGAGUUUUUUCCAACACCAUUUUUUUUUGUCUCUGAAAACACCAGCAGGCUGUGUCCAAGCAUGGGCUGAUGAUCCCUUUAUGUGAUGAUAGAACAAGGGAGGAGAGAGACAAAUUAAUGGGAUUGUUAAAAAUGGCUGAAAACUUGAUACUAACUUUGAGUCAGUAUUUUCUUUUUAAAGUCGUGUAAUACAAUAUUUGUAGAUAGGACAUUGAAAGUGAUGGGGGAAAUAAAUGUCUAUGCAGUGACGUUAUAGCCAUUAAUUCUUUAGUGGAAAAGGACAAGGUCUGUACCUAACAGCAGUAGGAGAGUGAGUUUUGGGGCCAGACACGCGACGGCUCUGCUGCCGACUAACUGUGCAAGCUUGGACAGGGUACCUACCUCUCUUAACCUCAAAGUCCUCCAUGGAAACAGUGGGUAAGGUGUGAAGAUUAAAGAAAUAGCACGCUUCUUAAAGCACUCAGCAUGUCAGUGGAUGUUGGGAGCCUUCCCUCACCCCUUUGAAAAUGGGCUCUGCACAAACACAUUUUGGUGGGAGGCUGGGGUCUAUCCUACCAACCUGAGUUGGGGGAAUAAGAUGAUCUCUUCCACAGUUCGGGUUUGCACAACCAGCUUUUGCAGGUGAGGCAGGGAAGAGGCAUGAGUGUCAUUGGCAGAGUGAUAAGCGAGGCUGGCAAGUUCACUUUGGUAGAACCUCUGUGGACUCCUUAGUUCUUCCAGGUUGAAUCCUGGGCAGAAAUCACAUGAAAGCUGUGAAGCACAGACAUCAGUUUAGAAAUUGUGUACUUUCCCGCUGAAUCCCAAAUGCACAAUAACUGUACACCUUGCGGUUGCAUGAAUCUACAAGGUCUCCUAUGCGCCCUCAUUCAUAAACUCAAGGCUGAGAAUGUUGGCAGGCCAAGUCCUGCCCCUCCCCGGAGUGAGCUGCCUUGGUUCACACGGGAGUGGUCCAGCGACAGGACCCGACACCUCCCCUCCGGAAGCUCUUCAGCAGGACCUGCCUCGGGUCCUGGGGCAGCUAUCCUCCGGGGCCUGCCUGCAGUGAAACCAUCAGUCCGUGGAGAUGUUCACUGGAUUCCUGACCAGUUGUGGGUCGGGCUCAACCCUCCCUCUGGGUUUUCAGGAUUUGUAAUGAUCGCUCCAUUUGUGUAAAAUAGGCCGGCAUUUUCUCUUGUUACUGAGAUGUAUUUUUCUAUGUGAGUUAAAUGUAUAAUUUGUGUAAUUUUGUACAUUAAAAUGUAUGCUUUUUCACAAUUAAAGGGUUUUUUUCCCUUCUGAA